AGCCUGAGAUGCAUAUGCUAGGAAGGCAGUUGGAUAAACAAAGCCUGGGAGGAUUUGAUCCAAAGGAUCGUUCAAGACUGCAGCAUAGAAACUGCAGUCACAGCAUCUAAAAUCAUGGGAUUGGAUGCCCCAAGGACAGUAUAUAGAUGCCUCAGUGACAUUUUGACUCUGAGGGAAAUACAGACGGAGUUGGUUAAUCAACCAUAGCUGGGUGCAAUGUAAGUGCCUGGCUGAAGUUUGACACGCGAACGGACGGCCCGCUGGAAUUCUGUGCUAUGAGCCGGAGUAGAAAGAGAGAUUUGGACUCUGCAACACCAAGGUAGUCGUUGAAGCCACAGUCGUGAAUGGAGACCAGGAGUGAAUAGUGGGAGUGAGCAGAAGUCGGAGGAUAGGACAGAAGAAGGCAGAGCCAUGGAGCACCCUGGAGAGGUGUGACCCGGCAAGAUCCUGAGAUGGAAGGUAGCACGGCCUGGAGUUCAGAAGCGGAGCCUCAAGAGGGAAGAAGCCAGAUGCUCCAGAGAGCAGGUGAGUUCCAGCAGCCAGGAGGUCGUCCGUGGCCUCGGUCGGGAGAUUGCGGUGGAGUGGCAUGGAUAAUACCUGAUGCCAGUGUGGUGAGGAUGGCAGACGGGGCCUUUUGAAUCUCAGCUGUGGGCAGGUAGAUGCUGCCUUUUUCUGCAUGGAGAAUUGACUUGGGAAUGUUGAUUUGCUGAAGAAAAGGAGCUUGAUGAAAUAGGAAGUCGGGUGGAAACAAACCUUAAAGAGGACAGGGCGAGUAGAAUGUGGGGACGUGAGAUGGCUUUGGACACUGGAAGGAAACCUUUUCCUCAGAGAGGGAACCUUGGAAGGAACCAGUAUGGGGGCUGCUGUGGAGAUGGAAUUCACAGUGCUUUCCCCAGCUUCUGACCGCCAUUUCUCUCAAUUGGACAGCACUGUGGCCACCUGAGAGUGAGCCGAGGAGGAGAGCGGGGCCUGGGGAAGCAGGGGUGGGGUUGGGGAGAGCGGGAGGCCGGCUGCCAGGUGAUGGCCCAGCCUUGCUGAGACUGGAACUGGGAGGCUAGGAACAGGACAAUGAGGAGGAUGACGGGAGUGACUGGGAACGUUUUAGAAGGAAAGUGAUGCAAUUAAAUUAAUAGUUUAGGAAGACAUGCAGUACCGGUGUACAGGGGGGAUCGGAGAAAGGGCUGGCAGAGUAAAUGUUCAUACACUCUGCAUUUAAAAAAUAUACUAAACACAAAGGUAUGCACAAUUCAGAUACUCAUCUUGAUGCAAGUUGACCAGUAGAGUCCAAUUGGGGUGGUAUCUUGAGGGUGGAAGAGUAUUUGAUAUGUGGAGCUGAGUGAGGGCAAGGUUCCAGAGAGGAGAGAGCCUGGACAGAGGCGCCAGGCUCAAGAUGCGCAGCCAGAAGUCAGGGCUCGUAGAGUAGGAGGAUCUCAUGGCUGGGGGGCUUUGUGCAGAGGAGAAGGGACGGAGAAAGCUGGCACGGUGGAUCAGGUCUUCCUUACGCACUGAGUCCAGCUUUGCAUUGGGGGAAGGCGUGGGGAGGUGCCAGAGGGCACGGUGUGGGGAGAUACCAUGACAUGCAGAUAUUUAGUGCAUGUUUCCUGCUCAUUGGUUUCUAUCUGCAUCAGAGCUGUGCCUUGCUUUCCUGGAGUUGCUGGCUCAUGAGGGAUCCAGACCUGAUGAGGGGCGUUCUGGAGAGCCGCUGGUAGAGACACGUGUGGUGGGGAAAGCUGUGCCCCGGGAUGGAGACGGAGGUCCCUCUGCGCUCCUGUGGAGCUCUCAGGCCCUGCAGCUCUCUGGCCUUUCUGCUCUGUCUCUCUCCACUUCCUCAGUGUGAUUCAGCGCAUGGCUGGUGCUUCUGCCCUGUGUCAUGGUAUCCUCCUGACUGGGAGUCUUUCCUCUUGGUUGCCACCAGUGCCCUGGAACCCUUUUUCCCUGCAUCUUCCUAGGCUUCGUCAUGGUCCGCUCAUCCGUGCUUCCAUCCUUGCUGGUGCUUACAGUUGUCUGCUUUCGUGUUUGUCUCCCAUUAGCCAAAGUGUUCCUUGCGGGUAGGAAGCAUGUUUCAUUCAUUUUCCUAACCUCAGUGCCGAGCAUGUUGCCAAGCAAAAUAAGUUGAAUGAAUGAAUAAAUAGUGAAGGUGCUUAAGUGAGGGAAUAUGACUGAAAUCGUCCUUUAAAAUAUUAAUUUUCCUAAAGGGAAAGAAAUAAUGAAAUACAUAAUGUGAUUGUAAAAUUUCACUGGCAUGACUUGAAACUUCAUUUUUGUUUCAUUUAUAAUAUUUUCAUGUAAUCCAAAUACACUAGUUGGCACCAGUGACCCAGGGCUUCUGAGCUACUGUGAACACAGCGUGUCCAUAUGCCCGAGCUGGUGGGGCAUGGCUUGGCGUGGAGCAGCCACCCUGAGUUGAUGGGAAGGAGGGAGAUAAGUGUUUAGAGCGUUCUGGAUGCCUCAGCUUCAUUUCCUGGGGCAGUGAUAAAAAGCUUUUUACUUUGAUGAAAACAUUUCUACACAGCAAAGUGAAAGUGUUGCUUAUGAAGGGCUGACGUGUUUGAAUAUGAUGAAUUAUUUACAAAAAUACAAGCGUAUUUGGCCCUUUAAAAGUUGGUAAGUACUGUGUAAGAAGCGGCUUUGCAUAAAGAGCAGUUUACUCUGUUGGAAAAAAAGAGACUAACAGGUAACUGCAGAGUUGCAGUCCAGGGAUGGGUGGAGGCUGGUGCAGAAUGGGAAAAAACAGCAUGGUAAUAUAGAAUUCAAGUUGUAGUUAUUGUAUAGGAUGUAAUUUGUGUUUCUGUAUUAUAGUUUUAGUAGCUUCUGAAAUAAACAUCUAAAGUGUUAUCCAAAAGGGCUUGAAGGCUGGGCGAGGUGGCUCUUGCCGGUAAUCCUAGCACUUUGGGAGGCUUAGGUGGGAGCACUGCUUGAGCCCGGGAGUUCUAGAUCAGCCUGGGCAACAUAGUGAGACCUUGUUUCUAAAAAAAAAAAAAAUAGCCCGGGAGGUUGAGGCUGCAGUGAGCCAUGAUCACACCAUUGCACUGUAGCCUGGGCAACAGAGGGAGACCCUGCCUCAAAAGACAAAAUGAACAACAACAAAAAAGAGCUUAGUUACUAUGGCUUCUUGGAUGUGCUAAUUACAUAUUGUAUUGGUGUCUCAGGGUUAUAUACAUUUCAAAUUUUCUUGGUGUCCCAGGACCAGAAGUUGUCUAAUCAGUCAUCAUAACUUUUUAGGACUAUACUCUGCUUCUCAGGGUUAAAUAUAUCUAAUUUUUAAAGGCAGAUUAAAGAUCUACUUAUAAAACCUCAGUAAUGAAGACAAGUGGUACUGGCAUGUGGAUAGGUAGACAAAUUAAUGCAACAGAACAGAAAAGUGUUAACAAACCCAGACACGUGGCAGAAUCUAAAGGAUGAUAUAAGUGUCAUUUCAUUUAGGAGAAGCAAAGAUAGACUACUGAAUACAUGAUUUGAGGAUACUAGGUAGUCAUCUAGAAAAAAAUAAAAAUAGAUUAUUCCAUGCAGAGCACCUCCAGGAUAGAUUCCAAAUGGAUUACAUAUGUACAUAUAUAGGUAUAUUUAUGUGUAUAUUUAAAUGCAAAAAGGAAAUCAUAAAAAGAAAAAAAAUGAGGAAAUUCCUUUCUAGCCUUGGAGUGAGGAGACCCUUUAAAUGGGACUCAAAAACCAGAAGUAAAGAAAAGAUUGAUAAGUUAAUCCACAUUCAAAAAACACAAUGAAACACCUUGGUAUUGCCCCAAAUCCUGUAAGCCAGGUCUUAGCAUGUUCCUGUUGAGGCCCUGGUGCCUCUCCUACCUCUCCACCUAUCUUUCUCCAUGUCCCAUAGCAUGCCAGAAGCUCCAACACCAUGUUAACAACUCCCUGUAGUUCUUGAAUUGUGGCCCUAGAGAAAACACUUAAAGCUCCUAUCACAGCAUAGUGCUAACCUUCUUAAUAUAUAAAGAGUUCCUAGAAAUGAUUAAGCAAAGAGCUCUUGGACAUGACUAAAAAAAAGAACAGCCUGAUAAAAAAUAGUCAAAGGAGAUGAACAAGACAAAUCACAACGGAAGGGAAGUAAAUGGCUCUUUGAAAACAUGAAAAGAUGCUCAGCCUUAUUCAUGGUAAGAGACAUGCAAUUGAAAAUAACACCUGUGAAAAUGGCACCUGUGACAUUUGCAAAUAUUCAUAAACUUCAUAACACACUGUUGGCAAGUCCACGAGGAGGCAGGUGCUUCUGUACUUUCCUGGUGGGAGUAUCAAGUGGUGUAGCUACCGAGGAAGGCAAUUUGGCAGUAUCCAUCAAUAUUAAAAAUGCAUGUUGGCUGGGCGUGGUGGCUCACGCCUAUAAUCCCAGCACUUUGGGAGGCCGAGGUGGGUGGAUCACGAGGUCAAGAGCUCAAGACCAUCCUGGCCAACAUGGUGAAAACCCAUUUCUACUAAAAAUACAAAAAGUAGCUGGGUGCGGUGGCACACACCUGUAGUCCCAGCUACUGGGGAGGCUGAGGCAGGAGAAUCGCUUGAACCCAGGGGGUGGAGGUUGCAGUGAGCUGAGAUCACACCACUGCACUCCAACCUGGCGACAAAAAAAAAAAAAUGCAUGUAACCAUUGAGUCAGUAAUUCUGCUUCUAGAUAUUUAUUACUCAGACAUACUCACACAUAGGCAAAGUGACUUAACAAGAUAUGAAUAUGGCGUAGUAUUGUUUGAAAUAGGACAUUGGAAACCAUCUAAUGGCCUGUCUACGAGUGGGCGCUUGGUUAAAUAACAUUUGCAGCAGUGUAAACGAAUGUCCAGAAGAUCUUCGAGAUACACCGUUAUGUGAAAAAAGCAAGGUGUAAACAACAUACACACACACUCAGAUACAUUUUUAUGUUAGAAAGGACAAUAAAAGCAUAUACUUGUAUUUGUGAUUGCGUAAAGAAACUGGGAAGAAACACAAGAAACUGUUUAUGUAACACUUGCUGGGCGGUAAAGGGAGGUGGAGGGGAGAAGGGGUCCUGGGGGAUGGAAAACCAGAGUUGUGGGGAGACUUUUCAGUGUUACCCCGUUUUAUACAUUUUGAUUUUUGAAUAAUAUAACUUAUCUCCCAUUCAAAAAUUAAAUUUCAGAAUUAGCAAGAAGGUACCGAAGUGGCAUUGAAUUAACGGUGAAUUGCCUUACUUUGCUGUUCACGUGUUCAUUAGGGGGUCAUGUUUUUAUGGUCUUCCUCCUGGGAUCAUGGUUUCAUUUGUCAGCCCCUAAAAUUUGAUCGAUUUCUGUCUUCCUCUGGCCUCCCACUUCUCCUACACAAGAUCCCAAAAUGUCAAACGAUGAAUAUUAAAAAAAUUGCACGCAUCACUACCCCUUGUGGUUAUCUUAUCAGCUCUUUUCUGACGUCAUGCACAGAUUUGAACGUGGAAAGCAUCACUUCUAUUUUAAUACAGUUUCUGACUGAUGCAAUUGAUGGUUUCAUGCUUAAGAUGUGAACUAUCGUUUAAACCACUGGAGAGCUGCCCAGCCAGUUUCAUCUGGUAGAAAUCACUACUUUUUAGAAAGAAACCAGAUGCCUUGUUGUAGAAACAUGAGCUUUAGAUACUAGCGCUUCUCCAGUGAGUGCAAAUGUAGCCUCAAGUGACAUUGACAUUUAAUGACACCACUAAAGGGGGCCCCAGCAAUUUAUUACAAGUUAUUCUGUUGUGACAGGGAUUUGAUUAGUUGACUGGACAGCAGGGGCAGUGGGCACCCCUGCACCUCUUCCUCAGCAGCUUUGCAGGGCAGAGUGGGAGCUGCUGUAUACCGGGGCUAGGGGUCUAGGCUGACCAGAACUCUGCCCUGGGAGAGCUUUCUGCCCAGGGCCAGAGGGACAAAGCCUUCCCUCUGGCUGGGCCUUCAUGGGGACACUUGAAUUAUUUAGAUUCCCGUGUUUGCCCUCCGCCCUGGUUUUCCUUGGGGUUUAGAGCUCAUGCUGUCUCUGGGAGUGUCUCAGUGGGCCUCUUUGCUGUCCCCUCACUGACUCUUCCCCCUUGGUUUGGAUAUCAUCCUGCUUAUUUUCCUGUGCUCUGCUUCUAGUGGUGACAGCUUUCUUUGUCUUAUCACUUAAUAUUAUUUCCUUCUAGUCCGCUGCUUGGUUUUAUUUUAGCUGCUACUUCCUUCCAAGUUACUGGAUUUUAUGAGAACCCUUUCCUGACCUUUAAACCUCCAUCUUCACUCCCCUUGCAAGCUUCUCCUUGGAGCUGCAAGCUCCUCGUGAGAUCUCUUCAGGUAACCCGUGGAGCACACCCAAGUCUCUGAAAGAAGCUAAUGGUAUAGAUAUAGAAGUCAUCCACAGAGAUGUUACAGUUGAAGAGAUGGGGGUAGAGAAGACUUUGAAGGAAAAGAAUGUAGAAUGAGGAUAGAAGAGAGGAAAUCCCAACAUUUAACAGGUUUGACAGAUGAAAAAGUGAAGGCAUAUCUUUCUCUUCACCCCCAGGUAUUAGAUGAAUUUGUAUCUGAAAGUGUUAGUGCAGAGACAGUAGAGAAAUGGCUGAAGAGGAAGAACAACAAAUCAGAAGAUGAAUCAGCUCCUAAGGAAGUCAGCAGGUACCAAGAUACGAAUAUGCAGGGAGUUGUAUAUGAACUAAACAGCUAUAUAGAACAACGGUUGGACACAGGAGGAGACAACCAGCUACUCCUCUAUGAACUGAGCAGCAUCAUUAAAAUAGCCACAAAAGCCGAUGGAUUUGCACUGUAUUUCCUUGGAGAGUGCAAUAAUAGCCUGUGUAUAUUCACGCCACCUGGGAUAAAGGAAGGAAAACCCCGCCUCAUCCCUGCUGGGCCCAUCACUCAGGGCACCACCGUCUCUGCUUAUGUGGCCAAGUCCAGGAAAACACUGCUAGUAGAAGACAUCCUUGGAGAUGAACGAUUUCCAAGAGGUACUGGACUGGAAUCAGGGACUCGUAUCCAGUCUGUUCUUUGCUUACCAAUUGUCACUGCAAUUGGUGACUUGAUUGGUAUUCUCGAGCUGUAUCGGCACUGGGGCAAAGAAGCCUUCUGUCUUAGUCACCAGGAGGUUGCAACAGCAAAUCUUGCCUGGGCUUCAGUAGCAAUACAUCAGGUGCAGGUAUGCAGAGGCCUUGCCAAACAGACAGAAUUGAAUGACUUCCUACUCGACGUAUCAAAAACAUAUUUUGAUAACAUAGUUGCAAUAGAUUCUCUACUUGAACACAUAAUGAUAUAUGCAAAAAACCUGGUGAAUGCCGAUCGUUGUGCGCUUUUCCAGGUGGACCAUAAGAACAAGGAGUUAUAUUCAGACCUUUUUGAUAUUGGAGAGGAAAAGGAAGGAAAACCUGUCUUCAAGAAGACCAAAGAGAUAAGAUUUUCAAUUGAGAAAGGAAUUGCUGGCCAAGUAGCAAGAACAGGGGAAGUCCUGAACAUUCCAGAUGCCUAUGCAGACCCACGCUUUAACAGAGAAGUAGACUUGUACACAGGCUACACCACGCGGAACAUCCUGUGCAUGCCCAUCGUCAGCCGAGGCAGCGUGAUAGGUGUGGUGCAGAUGGUCAACAAAAUCAGUGGCAGUGCCUUCUCUAAAACAGAUGAAAACAACUUCAAAAUGUUUGCCGUCUUUUGUGCUUUAGCCUUACACUGUGCUAAUAUGUAUCAUAGAAUUCGCCACUCAGAGUGCAUUUACCGGGUAACGAUGGAAAAGCUGUCCUACCAUAGCAUUUGUACUUCAGAAGAGUGGCAAGGUCUCAUGCAAUUCACCCUUCCCGUGCGUCUCUGCAAAGAAAUUGAAUUAUUCCACUUUGACAUUGGUCCUUUUGAAAACAUGUGGCCUGGAAUUUUUGUCUACAUGGUUCAUCGGUCCUGUGGGACAUCCUGCUUUGAGCUUGAAAAGUUGUGUCGUUUUAUUAUGUCUGUGAAGAAGAACUAUCGGCGGGUUCCUUAUCACAACUGGAAGCAUGCGGUCACUGUAGCACACUGCAUGUAUGCCAUACUUCAGAACAAUCACACGCUUUUCACAGACCUUGAGCGCAAAGGACUGCUGAUUGCGUGUCUGUGUCAUGACCUGGACCACAGGGGCUUCAGUAACAGCUACCUGCAGAAGUUCGACCACCCUCUGGCCGCUCUCUACUCCACUUCCACCAUGGAGCAGCACCACUUCUCCCAGACUGUGUCCAUCCUCCAGUUGGAAGGGCACAAUAUCUUCUCCACUCUGAGCUCCAGUGAAUAUGAGCAGGUGCUUGAGAUCAUCCGCAAAGCCAUCAUUGCCACAGACCUUGCUUUAUACUUUGGAAACAGGAAGCAGUUGGAAGAGAUGUACCAGACCGGAUCACUAAACCUUAAUAAUCAAUCACAUAGAGACCGUGUAAUUGGUUUGAUGAUGACUGCCUGUGACCUUUGUUCUGUGACAAAACUGUGGCCCGUUACAAAAUUGACGGCAAAUGAUAUAUAUGCAGAAUUCUGGGCUGAGGGUGAUGAAAUGAAGAAAUUGGGAAUACAGCCUAUUCCUAUGAUGGACAGAGACAAGAAGGAUGAAGUCCCCCAAGGCCAGCUUGGGUUCUACAAUGCCGUGGCCAUUCCCUGCUAUACAACCCUUACCCAGAUCCUCCCUCCCACGGAGCCUCUUCUGAAAGCAUGCAGGGAUAAUCUCAGUCAGUGGGAGAAGGUGAUUCGAGGGGAGGAGACUGCAACCUGGAUUUCAUCCCCAUCCGUGGCUCAGAAGGCAGCUGCAUCUGAAGAUUGAGCACUGGUCACCCUGACACGCUGUCCCACCUACAGAUCCUCAUCUUGCUUCUUUGACAUUCUUUUCCUUUUUUUGGGGGGGGUGGGGGGAACCUGCACCUGGUAACUGGGGUGCAAACCUCUUCAAGAAGGUAACAUCAAAUAAAUAAGUCAAGCAGAGGACUUCCUGCCAAUCUCUUCUGUGAGGCAUCAUAGACACUGAGCAACCAGGACCACCCCCACGUUCAGAAAUCAGCUGGCCAAGUGACUCCAUUUGACUUGCAAACCAGCCUUUUCUAAUAGGCUAAUAUUGCUGAGGCCUUAAAGGAAAUGGACAAAAAUUAUCCAGAAGGGGUACUUUUCCAUUGUAUCUUUCUAAUAAGGGUUUAAAAUGGUACUAUUAUGGUAUUGUACUUGGGCUUUAACAUCAAUGUUGCUUUGAUGUUGUUGGAUAUAAAUAGGAAUUUUUACACAUUACUAUUGUGAAUGGUGAAUGUUCAUGUAUGACCUACUUGUAAUUAACUUGAGUUGUAGUCCACAGCCUCAGGACAAAUGUCGUUGAGGUUACAGAGUAAGAAAUGAUGGCAAAACGUCAAACUCUUAUUUCAGAGCUUCAUGAAUUUAGUUAGACUAAACAUAAUUCUUUAAGUUCAACCUAAAGGGCUGAGAUCAAUAAAUUUAACACUAGACGAAGUAGACUUCCUGUCUUUUUGAGAAGAGAUGAGGUAUAUGUUACAAUAAAUCUCAGAACUUCAAGUAGCAGUUCAAAAGAUGUCAGUUUUUAAAAUUGUUUUUGUUGUUGUCUUGGCAGUUUUACUGAACCCUUUGCAUAAAGAACAAAAUAAAAGCUCGGCAUUGUAAUUUUUUUAAUGGACAAGUCUUAUGGAUACGAAGGGUACAUUUUUCAUAAUGAUUCCUUUAUAUUUUCACUUUGUGUCAUUGCAGAAUUUUAGACUCUCAUUCACAAUGAAAAGUUUAUUUUAAACAUUGUUUAAUUAAAAUACCAUACAGUUCUCUUUUAAACAUCAAACCAUAAAAAGUGUAUUUUGUAAUUUUACUCUGACCUGCCGCAGUCACCUCUCACUUAUCUCUUCCACGUACUGCACGGUCGUAUUUCAUGAGCUUUCUGUCCAUAGCACAGAAACAGAGCAGAAAGUAGUACAAUCAUGUUGGACCUUCUUUCUGUUCUCUUUACUCUUCUCACAGAUCAGAUCACUCCAUAGAAGCCUGUGGGUUUCGAUGGUUUCUUCUAUACACCUUUUUGGUUGACCAGUAUUACUAUACAAUGUAAGUGUUUUAAAAAAUACGAAAGUAAUACUCUGCACCCCUUCCUACAAAGAUGAUAAAGCAGUCACUUCUGGCGCAUUUUAAUAAUUUAAAGAUUUUUAGUGCAAUGGCACGGUAACCUCCAAACCUGAAUUAGACAGAGACUCACUCAGGAAGUGACAGGCCCAUCAUAUCAAAUAACUUAUUCACUUUUCAUGUGGCAGGAAACUGGAAUAUCGCUUUUAAUAAAAUGGAAAAAUAUGCUUCUACAUAUUUACCACCAUAGGCGUUUUGUUCAUAUGAGCCUGGUUUGUGCAAAAUUAAAUCAGAGGCUUCUACAACAUGGUUUAUUUAUGUUGUAGCAAAGUUGGCUCUACAUAAACAUUGUUCUUAUUUUAAAAUUAACACUAUGUGUUCAGUUUUCUUGUGGGCUUCUGAAAGUUGCCAUCUUCCCUCCGUGGAGCUCCAUUUGCUAUUUUCAUUAUACACUAUGAGGUAAAAUGUAAUAACAAAAGAGAGAGAAGUACCACUGUGGCUAGAUAUAUACACACACAUAUAUAUAUGGAUGGAUGUAAUAUAUGUAGAACACACACAUAGAUGUAUAUAGGAUACACACUCAUGUAUGUAAACGUAUACAUAUGUGUAUAUAUGAUACAUACACAUACACACACACGAGAGACAGAAGGAAAGAGAGGAAGAGAGAAGCAAACAUGUAGGAAAAAAUAUAAAUCAGCCCCAUUCUCCCAUUCUUUAAGAACAAUGAUUUUUCUUGAUGGAAAAUGCAUAUCACUUGACAGUUGACAAGAAAGUGUCAUUUUUGUGUUAGUGUAUCAUAUAAUUGAAUUUGAACAAGAUACAUAUUUUUCUGCAUACAAAUUUAUGAAGCUGGAGUCUACCAAACACAGCUUUAGUCACAAAAGUUAGUUUAGUUAUCUCAUUUCGCUUGGAGAUGGAAUUUCAGGAAGGGAUAUAUUAUUUAAGAUUAUUGUUUAAUUACAAGAAUUUUAAAAGAAUGUAUGAAUUCUGUUUUUUAAUAUAGAAAAUAAUUAUGGAGUUAGGAAUCUCAUGGCUACAUUUACAUUUUUAGGUUAUUACAGAAAAUUCUCUUAAUUUAUUAUAGUCAAGUGUAUUAUGUAAUCUCUAUUUAGAACAGUUUCCCAAAGGAAUGUGAUUGGAUUUACUGGUUGGUUAAUUUCUUGUGAAAUAUUGUCAUAAUAGAAGCACAGCUUGAACAAAAGACUGAAUUCUGAUAUAAACUGUCAAUAUUGCUUUUACCAUGUGUAAGAUUUACUUAGUAAUCACAGAUUUACCUAAAAUAAAAGGACCCGGGUUGCAGUGAUAUUUAGUUAAUGAUUUGUUUUGGAAAACAUGCAGUUAGGAGUAUUUUUGUAUUUUGUCAGAUGUUUAGGAGACAGACUUUCGGGUCAUGUUUCUUGUCUUGUUCCCAGAUCUUUUCUUAAAAGAACAGUGUGACACCAGAAGCCAAGAGAUGGUUUUUACUAACAACAGCUUUGAUGAGUUCCUAUUAAGGUCGUAUUGUGUAUUGUGCCAAAUUUUCCACCCAGUAUAAAUUUAGUAACCCGCUAUGAGCAUAUGUAGGAUAUUCAAUUUGCAGAUACUUUUGUUGGUUAUGUUGGUUUAUAAUAGACAAGUUUUAUGGUCAUAUGCAAUUAUUCCAUUAUCUUUUUGGACACAGUGAAUAUGUUUUUUAGCUAAAAAUGUCCUUGGAAACAUAAAUGCCUGCCAAUAACAUGGAAUAUUGAAUUCGGGCAAUGUGAAUUGAUUAAUUAGAAAAGGGUCAAAAGAAAUACAAUGGAUGUGGAAACUAAUUCUAAAAAAUAGCCCUAUUAAUAGGGCAGAGACUCUGGUCCAUUUCCCAGCUGUACUUCUCUCUAAGAGGUGUAUGAAAAACCCAUCUUGCAAAAGAGACCAAAAUAUUAGACACAAUCGUUCCCAUUCCUGACUCUUCAAUGGAAAAGGAAGGUACAGAUGUUUACAGUGGUGCCCCAGGUGACUCGUUCUCACCACAACAAAAGCAACUAAUUGGAAACUAGAUGUGUUCAAUAAUAGAUUUCCUCUUUUUUGGCAUGCUUUUUAGAUUUUUUUUCAUUUUGUAAAAUCUCAGUUAAUUUUUCUUUAUUGGUAUAUUUGUGUAUGCGAGACAAAUCCUGUAUUGUACAGGAUAUAAAUAGAUGCAUAAAUCCUUAGAUACCUGGGUUUUUUAAUAGGUUUAGGUUUGGGUAUUGUGUUUCUGGUCUUUUAACUCAAAAUUAAGGUUUGAGCUUUAAUAGGACUAAAUUAUUCACCUGCCUUGGCCUGUGCCUUUAUUUUAAAUACUGCAAUUUUACUUCUUCAUUCAUGUAUUUAUUAUUUUGCUUUUCUUGCUUAAGUAUAAUUGAAAAUAUUUGCAGGAACGCACAAUUCAUUUUAUCAAGUUGAAUGAAUAGGACCAUUCUCUCCUCAUCAGAUUUCUGUUCUUUAUUUGACUUCAUUGACAUAUACCCUGGUGACUAUAACCAGUGAACUGUUCAGAGUCAGUCUUUUCGGCAAGAACUUCAGAGAACUGUGACACUGGUUAUGAUGUGAUUUUGGGGGGUUUCAGGUACCUAAGCAUGAUUUUUAAAAUCACUUCUCUCUUUACAUAUUUCGAACAUAUGUUUGCUUUCUACACUUUGCAGAUUUUAUUUAGGAUUUAAUUCUUUAAAGACUAUAUUCAUUUAGUCACUAUAGUGGAUCUCUUCUACUGCAAGUAUUCAUCUGAUUUUUAAAUUAUGUAAAAUGUAAAUCAGCCAAGUAUGUCAUCCGUUAUAGUUUCCCCAUGCUUUCAGCGCAUGGCCAUGAGAUUUUUACAUGUGCAUAAGUAUUUAGCCAAUACACAUUUUGCUGACUUCUUUAACCAUUUAUAUUGUUUAAAUUAGUAAUAUCCAAUGCAGUGCACACUUUUUUGUCUUUUUUCCAACGGAAUAUUUUGGUUGUCUGUAGCGUUGGAAGCAUUUUAUAUGAUAAAAAUAGCAAGAAAAAAUUAAAAAGUGUCAACGGUGUGCUGGUUCUAAAUUAAGAAGAUAGAACAAAGAGAAAGACAUUAAUGUUACCUAAGAAACACAUUUAACAUCCGAAGAAGCAAUGCUGUCCUCACUUGAUGUUUCUCUUCUCAACCCAGCAAUGGAGAGCAGGGCUUGCAAAGCCGUACAGAGCCUACGUGCUCUUUCCUGCAAGUGGGAGAAAACUAAUCAAUGGCACACAGGGCCAGGUGUGGCCCUGUGAGGCAAAGGAUAAUGUCACCUCAGGACCAAGGUGGAAACUUACAGCUGAAUCCAGGGCUUACUAAGUAGGGAAGUCAGUUUACAUAUUUCAGUUUUCCUCUGAUGUUUUUGAGGUACUGUGUAUUUGCAGAAGUUUAAGCAGAAGGGUUUUGUUUCUAUUGUAAGUUAGGUUCUAAAAGUGUAUAAUCUGAUACUCUAGCCCAACUGAAAUAUUAUAUCUUGGGCGUUACAGCCUUUGUCUUUUUCUUUAGUCACCUUAAUACCCAGUCCUAUGCUGUAUCUCUGAUAGCCUAUAUAAAUGACAUAUAGGAAUAUUAUUUUCCAUAUGAUCUGUUGUAUGGUGUAUAUGCUAUGUGUUCAUUUCGUGUGCAAGUUCAGAGUGUAAUAGAUUUACCCAGAGAAGGUGUUUCUAUACAAUGCCCCUACCUAUUUGAAAUUACAUGCUUGCCCAACACACUGUGAAAUAGUUACCAAAAUUUGUACAAAUGCAGCAUCUUCAUUCUUUCUGAGAAGACAAGAUGGUUUUCUUUACAUGAACAAAUGAACAAAAGAGAUCCUAGAUCCAUAACGUAGCUAAGGCAUCUAAGAGUUUGCUGUUGAUAAUCUUGCUGACCAAAAACUACUGGAGAGUAACACAGGUUAUAUGCCAUCACAAAUACAAUGCUCAUGAAGAACUGAUUUGUAGAGUCAAUGAACCUGUGUCCAGAAUUUUAAUAGGCUCUCUAUUGGAAGGAGAAAGAAUUUCAAGUUAACAGUAUCUAACUUUAUCAUAGUUGAUGUUAGUAAAUUUUAAAAAAUGAUUUUAUAUGUAUGACAAAAAUCUUUGUAAAAUGCGCAAGUGCAAUAAUUUAAAGAGGUCUUAACUUUGCAUUUAUAAAUUAUAAAUAUUGUACAUGUGUGUAAUUUUUUCAUGUAUUCAUUUGCAGUCUUUGUAUUUAAAAAACAUUUACUGUUAUGUUUGUAUAAUAGAACAGUAAUCAUUUAUUAUAAUCUAGGCAAGUUGUAAAUAAAUUCAUAAUUCAAACAGCCAGUAUAUAUGCAUAUAUGAGUGUUAUAUUGCAAAAUCUUUGUUUUACUUACAUGGUUAAAGCAGCAAGAAUUCUUUUGUUGAUAUGUAAUUAUACACAUAAAAUAUAUAUAUGUAUGAUACAUGAAAUAUAUUUAGAAAUGUUCAUAAUUUUAAUGGAUAUCCUUUGGUGUGAAUAAUUGAAUACAGAGUUUUUAAAAUA